GCAGCAGCCGCAGCGCCGGCCGCGGCUCCGGCUCCGGCUCCGGCUCCCGGGCAUUUAAAGGGGACGCGGCGGCUGCCCGGGGGGGAUGAGGGGCAAGUGGAGGGGACGGCUCAGACGCACAUCAUCCUCAGUCCCUCGGGACUGGAGGGACUCGUGAGCCGGAGCCCAGAAAUCCGGGGGUGGAUAAGACACCGCGUCCCCUCCAAUUCCCGUAAGCACCCCUUGCUCCAUCCUGCGCCCCAAUACCUCAGCUAGCCCCCUUCCCCACUUCUUACACUCCAAACUCAGCCGGGACAGACCUCUGCUGCCGCCGCCCCCACGAACGUGUGACGACGGCUGGAGGCCAACAGAGUCCCUACAGGUGGUGCUCACGGUAAUGCACCGACAAUGAGUGGCUGUUUUCCAGUUUCUGGCCUCCGCUGCCUAUCUAGGGUGUGUCAUGGCCUGGUGCGGGAGGCUCUUACCUCCCCAAGCCCCACUGCUUCUCCUGCUGCCCGCUUGCUUCGGACUCUGGCAGAAACCCCACCUGCUGACACGUUCCUCCUGGGGAAUUGGUGUUGGAUGUGCCAGCGCCUCUGGCCGUGGCCCGCUAACCAGCCUCUCCCGGGCGGGCUCCUGCCGCGCCCCCUCUCGCUUGCCCCCUCCUCCUCCUCCUCCUGCUGCUCUCCCCCCUGCUCCCAGGACGGCAGGAUGGCCGCGCAGGGCGCGCCGCGCUUCCUCCUGACCUUCGACUUCGACGAGACUAUCGUGGACGAAAACAGCGACGAUUCGAUCGUGCGCGCCGCGCCGGGCCAGCGGCUCCCGGAGAGCCUGCGAGCCACCUACCGCGAGGGCUUCUACAACGAGUACAUGCAGCGCGUCUUCAAGUACCUGGGCGAGCAGGGCGUGCGGCCGCGGGACCUGAGCGCCAUCUACGAAGCCAUCCCUUUGUCGCCAGGCAUGAGCGACCUGCUGCAGUUUGUGGCAAAACAGGGCGCCUGCUUCGAGGUGAUUCUCAUCUCCGAUGCCAACACCUUUGGCGUGGAGAGCUCGCUGCGCGCCGCCGGCCACCACAGCCUGUUCCGCCGCAUCCUCAGCAACCCGUCGGGGCCGGAUGCGCGGGGACUGCUGGCUCUGCGGCCGUUCCACACACACAGCUGCGCGCGCUGCCCCGCCAACAUGUGCAAGCACAAGGUGCUCAGCGACUACCUGCGCGAGCGGGCCCACGACGGCGUGCACUUCGAGCGCCUCUUCUACGUGGGCGACGGCGCCAACGACUUCUGCCCCAUGGGGCUGCUGGCGGGCGGCGACGUGGCCUUCCCGCGCCGCGGCUACCCCAUGCACCGCCUCAUUCAGGAGGCCCAGAAGGCCGAGCCCAGCUCGUUCCGCGCCAGCGUGGUGCCCUGGGAAACGGCUGCAGAUGUGCGCCUCCACCUGCAACAGGUGCUGAAGUCGUGCUGAGUCUGGCCGCCUGCAGGGGGGUACCCGGGCCAACGGCGGAGGGGGCGGGGAAGGGAGAUUCGGCAAAGACAGCUUUACUACUCCCUUUUCCCUUUGGCUUUGUUAUGUCCCUCUGGGAAUUUCUGGAAUCUCGUAUUUGGGGGCUUGGGGAAGGGGGCUCAGAGCCGUCCCUAUCUAUUCAGUUAACCCACCUCGGCUGCCUCCCCCACUCCACUGUGCACGGUUGAGUUCUGGAGUCUGACCCAUCGCGGGGUGGCGCGCAAACCUUGGAAGGCAGCAGUAUUUCCUGGUCCUCCCAACUGGGAGGAAGGGGCCCCCCCGGCAGGUGAGAGAAGGAACAUCUCCCGCCGCUGUAACUUGUUGCCUCGGGCUGCGUGACCGCCCCUCCUCCAGUCUACUGUGGAGGGAACCCAGGAUCCUGAAAUUCUCCUGGCCGCAAGAACUCCCCACAGAGGCAGAAGAGGGUCUCCACCUAUGGCCCCAGGCCUUUGCGAUCUUGCUUCACCCACCGCGACCCCACACUAUUUCUGUGCUGUCCACACUCUCUUGCCUCCCGACCCCCGCACUCCCUUCUAGCACCCCCAAAGGAAAAGCCAGAGGAACAAUCGCCUCCUGGUGGUGGUACGAGGUAGCGCACCGUCCGGCUCGGGUCCGGACAGCCAGUAACCUCGCAGAGAGUGACGGUGUCUCCUUGCAUCCCAGCCUCGUCUAUGCAGCAAGAGACCAGGGACUUCACCAAAGUCACCCUCGCGGGCUGGGCCUUCCACGCAUCCCCCCCACCCCCCAUGGAACAGAAAGCCAUGUUUUUAAGCAGAACCAGCGAAACCCAAGCCCCUCCUUCCUCUGGUGUUUUACAACUAUAAAGGAGGUGAAGGGGGAA